AGUUGCUGCUGCAGCUGAGGUACAGCGGCGGUUUCUGAGGUUCUUCACUCGCGACUGACGGAGCUGCGGUGGCGUCUCCACACGCAACCAUGAAGUUGAAGGACACAAAAUCAAGGCCAAAGCAGUCAAGCUGUGGCAAAUUUCAGACAAAGGGAAUCAAAGUUGUGGGAAAAUGGAAGGAAGUGAAGAUUGACCCAAAUAUGUUUGCAGAUGGACAGAUGGAUGACUUGGUGUGCUUUGAGGAAUUGACAGAUUACCAGUUGGUCUCCCCUGCCAAGAAUCCCUCCAGUCUCUUCUCAAAGGAAGCACCCAAGAGAAAGGCACAAGCUGUUUCAGAAGAAGAGGAGGAGGAGGAGGGAAAGUCUAGCUCACCAAAGAAAAAGAUCAAGUUGAAGAAAAGUAAAAAUGUAGCAACUGAAGGAACCAGUACCCAGAAAGAAUUUGAAGUGAAAGAUCCUGAGCUGGAGGCCCAGGGAGAUGACAUGGUUUGUGAUGAUCCGGAGGCUGGGGAGAUGACAUCAGAAAACCUGGUCCAAACUGCUCCAAAAAAGAAGAAAAAUAAAGGGAAAAAAGGGUUGGAGCCUUCUCAGAGCACUGCUGCCAAGGUGCCCAAAAAAGCGAAGACAUGGAUUCCUGAAGUUCAUGAUCAGAAAGCAGAUGUGUCAGCUUGGAAGGACCUGUUUGUUCCCAGGCCGGUUCUCCGAGCACUCAGCUUUCUAGGCUUCUCUGCACCCACACCAAUCCAAGCCCUGACCUUGGCACCUGCCAUCCGUGACAAACUGGACAUCCUUGGGGCUGCUGAGACAGGAAGUGGGAAAACUCUUGCCUUUGCCAUCCCAAUGAUUCAUGCGGUGUUGCAGUGGCAGAAGAGGAAUGCUGCCCCUCCUCCAAGUAACACCGAAGCACCACCUGGAGAGACCAGAACUGAGGCCGGAGCUGAGACUAGAUCACCAGGCAAGGCUGAAGCUGAGUCUGAUGCAUUGCCUGACGAUACUGUAAUUGAGAGUGAAGCACUGCCCAGUGAUAUUGCAGCCGAGGCCAGAGCCAAGACUGGAGGCACUGUCUCAGACCAGGCGUUGCUCUUUGGUGACGAUGAUGCUGGUGAAGGGCCUUCUUCCCUGAUCAGGGAGAAACCUGUUCCCAAACAGAAUGAGAAUGAGGAGGAAAAUCUUGAUAAAGAGCAGACUGGAAAUCUAAAACAGGAGUUGGAUGACAAAAGCGCCACCUGUAAGGCAUAUCCAAAGCGUCCUCUGCUUGGACUGGUUCUGACUCCCACUCGAGAGCUGGCCGUCCAGGUCAAACAGCACAUUGAUGCUGUGGCCAGGUUUACAGGAAUUAAAACUGCUAUUUUGGUUGGUGGAAUGUCCACGCAGAAACAGCAGAGGAUGCUGAACCGUCGUCCUGAGAUUGUGGUUGCUACUCCAGGCCGGCUGUGGGAAUUAAUUAAAGAAAAGCAUUAUCAUUUGAGGAACCUUCGGCAGCUCAGGUGCCUGGUAGUGGAUGAGGCUGACCGGAUGGUUGAGAAAGGCCAUUUUGCUGAGCUCUCACAGCUGCUAGAGAUGCUCAAUGACUCCCAAUACAACCCAAAGAGACAAACGCUUGUUUUUUCUGCCACACUCACCCUGGUGCAUCAGGCUCCUGCUCGAAUCCUUCAUAAGAAGCACACCAAGAAAAUGGAUAAAACAGCCAAACUUGACCUCCUUAUGCAGAAAAUUGGCAUGAGGGGCAAGCCCAAGGUCAUUGACCUCACAAGGAAUGAGGCCACGGUGGAGACGCUAACAGAGACCAAGAUCCAUUGUGAGACUGAUGAGAAAGACUUCUACUUGUACUACUUCCUGAUGCAGUAUCCAGGCCGCAGCUUAGUGUUUGCCAACAGUAUCUCCUGCAUCAAACGCCUCUCUGGGCUCCUCAAAGUCCUUGAUAUCAUGCCCUUGACCCUGCAUGCCUGUAUGCACCAGAAGCAGAGGCUCAGAAACCUGGAGCAGUUUGCCCGUCUGGAAGACUGUGUUCUCUUGGCAACAGAUGUGGCAGCUCGGGGUCUGGAUAUUCCUAAAGUCCAGCAUGUCAUCCAUUACCAGGUCCCACGUACCUCGGAGAUUUAUGUCCACCGAAGUGGUCGAACUGCUCGAGCUACCAAUGAAGGCCUCAGUCUGAUGCUCAUUGGGCCUGAGGAUGUGAUCAACUUUAAGAAGAUUUACAAAACGCUCAAGAAAGAUGAGGAUAUCCCACUGUUCCCCGUGCAGACAAAAUACAUGGAUGUGGUCAAGGAGCGAAUCCGUUUAGCUCGACAGAUUGAGAAAUCUGAGUAUCGGAACUUCCAGGCUUGCCUGCACAACUCUUGGAUUGAGCAGGCAGCAGCUGCCCUGGAGAUUGAGCUGGAAGAAGACAUGUAUAAGGGAGGAAAAGCUGACCAGCAAGAAGAACGUCGGAGACAAAAGCAGAUGAAGGUUCUGAAGAAGGAGCUGCGCCACCUGCUGUCCCAGCCACUGUUUACGGAGAGCCAGAAAACCAAGUAUCCCACUCAGUCUGGCAAGCCGCCCCUGCUUGUGUCUGCCCCAAGUAAGAGCGAGUCUGCUUUGAGCUGUCUCUCCAAGCAGAAGAAGAAGAAGACAAAGAAGCCGAAGGAGCCACAGCCGGAACAGCCACAGCCAAGUACAAGUGCAAAUUAACUGGUCAAGUGUGUCAGUGACUGCACAUUGGUUUCUGUUCUCUGGCUAUUUGCAAAACCUCUCCCACCCUUGUGUUUCACUCCACCACCAACCCCAGGUAAAAAAGUCUCCCUCUCUUCCACUCACACCCAUAGCGGGAGAGACCUCAUGCAGAUUUGCAUUGUUUUGGAGUAAGAAUUCAAUGCAGCAGCUUAAUUUUUCUGUAUUGCAGUGUUUAUAGGCUUCUUGUGUGUUAAACUUGAUUUCAUAAAUUAAAAACAAUGGUCAGAGCCAUUGUGUCAUCCUGAUUUUUUUUUUUUUUUUUUAGAUAGAAGAUGGGGGUGGUGGUGUAGUUUGUUUCAUUAUUAACUUAGUGAUUCUCCUGGGCCAGCACAGUGCUAAGCCCUUGAAAGGACAGGAAUAGUGUCAGGCCUCUGGCUGCAGGCCAAGAUUGGACAGUGUGAAUGGAGCAAGAGGCUGGAAUGUUCAAGAGGUGCAUGUUCCUGCUUUACCCAGAGCAGCACCCUAAUAGCUCCUUAGCUCUCUCCACUCUCCUGGGUAUUGUCUGAGCCACCGUGGGAGGUGGGCAGGGAUGAGGUUGCUGUCUUCAGGCUUCCCUCACAUCACAGAGCCAACAGUAACAGUCGCUAGGUCUGGCGUGUGAAGCCCUCAGGAUCUAGCCCCAGCCUUGUCUCCACUCCCUCCUGUUUGACAGAGCAGGCUCCUGCCCACGGUUCCAUGCACCCCUUCUCUUGUCCUGAGCCUUUGUGCAGAAUAGGCUUUUCCCUCGGUCUGGAUUGCCUUUUGGCCUUCUCCAUCCUGGAGCACUGCCAUGGGUCCUCUAGUCCUGAGCCUCUAAGGGGAAGCAGUGCUUCUCCUGGGGCUCCCUUAGUGUCCCGUGCUUACCCUCUUCAUAGCACUUGCCAUGCUGUGUUCCCUUAGCUGAGCUCCUUGGGAGAAGAGGAACUCAAGGCUUGGUCAGCCUGGUAUAAAUAUGUGCUCAGGGAACUAGGGACUUCCUGAUGCUGCCCCAGCUUUGUCUGGAUCAGUGUAGGUGAGUAUCCACAACUCCCACAACCAUGGGAGAAGCAUAGAUGAUUUCUGCACAGCUGUCUGGCUUCCAAACAGGUAUUCGUCGGGGCACAAUACAAUACAGCUGUUUAGUUCAAGGGGUGCUAGGGAAUUGAAGAGGAUACACAAAGGGACCAAGAUACCCCAAGAUCUAAGUAGCUAGCCUCUCUCAGCCUCAUGGUUGGCACUUUUAUCUAAUUAGCAUUUAGUCUUGAAGGUCCUGAGAAAUAAUUUUCUUUUUUUUUUGAGACAGGGUCUUGCUCCAUUGCCCAGGUUGGAGUGCAAUGGCACAAUCACAGCUCACUGCAACCUCACACUCCUGGGCCCAGGCAGUCCUCCCGCCUCAGCCUCCCAAGUAGCUGGGACUACAGGCACACACCACCACACCUGGCUGAAUUUUUUUUUUUUAGUAGAGAUGGGGUCUCACUAUGUUGGCGUAGGCUGGUCUCAAAACUCCUGCCCUCAAGUGAUCCUCUUGCCUCAGCCUCCCAAAGUACUGAGAUUACAGGUGUGAGCCACUGUGCCCAUCUAUAAGUCUUUAUUAGUGUUUUUUGUACUUGAGCAUAUAGACACCCAGUGAUUGAGACUUGCCCAGGGCCACACAGCAGCCAAGUAGCAGAGGUGGGAUUAGUAUCUUCCUUCUGGGCCCAGGACAAGUUCAGAAAACUACUUCAGUCUCAGAAGUGUUGCCAAGGAAUGGCCUCCCAUCCCCCAGUGUCACCAGUGACCGGAAUAGGAGGGGAAAUUGCCCGUCUGUGAGGUCAGCUCCUGACUGACAGCUAUCAGAGAAUGGCAGGGAGACUCUCCAUUUUCCAAAUGAUGCAGUGGUGGUCAGUGGGGUUAGUAAGCGGGCUUAAUAUCCCCUAAUGGCACCUGAGCCGUGGGAGUGAAGCCACUUGCCAUAAGCCAAACAUAGAUCCCCUGAUGACUGUCCGUGUCCUGCCCUAGCCAUCUAACAGCAAAUUCUUUUCCUUGGUGGAGGAGCUAAUACGUAGACAGGCUUUAAAAGGCAGGAGCAGCCUUCCAAGCAGUGCUACUCUCGCCUGGUAAGGUGAAGUUGGUGGGCAGAGCUUCCGGAGUGUCCUGGAUCUGCCAUUAAACAAGGAAUAUCCCUCCCCAGCUAAUCUACUUAAUACAUAAGCACCACGGAAAAGCAGAGUUCUUGGCUGCAUGCCAGGUACCCAGUAUUAAGAAGCCAGGACAAAAGUAGUUAUGGAAACCAUUUUAAUGCUAGGAGAAUGUUUUUACUUACUGCCUAGGGAAGCUGUAGGGCUUGGCCCACAUCCAGCAGGGCCUGGGGCCCCUGGAAGCCACUCACUGAGUUACAGCCCCCUCCCCACUCCUGUAUCUGCUCAGGGUGGUGAUGUGUUUGCUCCUAGACUCUCUCUCAUGGUUCCCCUGACACUCCUGCUUGGGAAGCCACCGAGUCACUGCCAAGGUGACAUGCUUCCCCAUCUGCAGUGCCCUAUGCUUCCUGUCAGGAAGGACAGGUUGGGGAAUAUCCCUUUGCAGAGCCCAUACGAUGAGUGUGUCAGGUAUAAUAGCUAUUUUCACACAAGGAAUCUCAUUCUGUUUUAACCAAUAAUCCAGUGACACAUAGGUAUUGUUGCCAUUUCACAAACUUGGGAAUUGGGGCUCAGGGAGGUGAAGUGACUUGGCCAAGAUCAUACAGCUAGUAAGUGAAUGCUGAAGUUAGAACCCUGGCAUUCUGGCUCCAGAGCUCUCAUUUGUGCUUAAAAUAGGAACCCAGUCAAAAGCAGGGACUGUGCUCUUUCUGUUGCUAAUUGUUCCCAUUGAUUUAAAAGUUUCCUUUGGAGAGAAAGUAUCAUAAUAAACAUGCAGUUGUAAAAACAA